ACAGAAGGAGGAAGGACAGCAGGGCCAACAGUCACAGCAGCCCUGACCAGAGCAUUCCUGGAGCUCAAGCUCCUCUACAAAGAGGUGGACAGAGAAGACAGCAGAGACCAUGGGACCCCCCUCAGCCCCUCCCUGCAGAUUGCAUGUCCCCUGGAAGGAGGUCCUGCUCACAGCCUCACUUCUAACCUUCUGGAACCCACCCACCACUGCCAAGCUCACUAUUGAAUCCACGCCGUUCAAUGUCGCAGAGGGGAAGGAGGUUCUUCUACUCGCCCACAACCUGCCCCAGAAUCGUAUUGGUUACAGCUGGUACAAAGGCGAAAGAGUGGAUGGCAACAGUCUAAUUGUAGGAUAUGUAAUAGGAACUCAACAAGCUACCCCAGGGCCCGCAUACAGUGGUCGAGAGACAAUAUACCCCAAUGCAUCCCUGCUGAUCCAGAACGUCACCCAGAAUGACACAGGAUUCUAUACCCUACAAGUCAUAAAGUCAGAUCUUGUGAAUGAAGAAGCAACCGGACAGUUCCAUGUAUACCCGGAGCUGCCCAAGCCCUCCAUCUCCAGCAACAACUCCAACCCCGUGGAGGACAAGGAUGCUGUGGCCUUCACCUGUGAACCUGAGGUUCAGAACACAACCUACCUGUGGUGGGUAAAUGGUCAGAGCCUCCCGGUCAGUCCCAGGCUGCAGCUGUCCAAUGGCAACAUGACCCUCACUCUACUCAGCGUCAAAAGGAACGAUGCAGGAUCCUAUGAAUGUGAAAUACAGAACCCAGCGAGUGCCAACCGCAGUGACCCAGUCACCCUGAAUGUCCUCUAUGGCCCAGAUGUCCCCACCAUUUCCCCCUCAAAGGCCAAUUACCGUCCAGGGGAAAAUCUGAACCUCUCCUGCCACGCAGCCUCUAACCCACCUGCACAGUACUCUUGGUUUAUCAAUGGGACGUUCCAGCAAUCCACACAAGAGCUCUUUAUCCCCAACAUCACUGUGAAUAAUAGCGGAUCCUAUAUGUGCCAAGCCCAUAACUCAGCCACUGGCCUCAAUAGGACCACAGUCACGAUGAUCACAGUCUCUGGAAGUGCUCCUGUCCUCUCAGCUGUGGCCACCGUCGGCAUCACGAUUGGAGUGCUGGCCAGGGUGGCUCUGAUAUAGCAGCCCUGGUGUAUUUUCGAUAUUUCAGGAAGACUGGCAGAUUGGACCAGACCCUGAAUUCUUCUAGCUCCUCCAAUCCCAUUUUAUCCCAUGGAACCACUAAAAACAAGGUCUGCUCUGCUCCUGAAGCCCUAUAUGCUGGAGAUGGACAACUCAAUGAAAAUUUAAAGGGAAAACCCUCAGGCCUGAGGUGUGUGCCACUCAGAGACUUCACCUAACUAGAGACAGUCAAACUGCAAACCAUGGUGAGAAAUUGACGACUUCACACUAUGGACAGCUUUUCCCAAGAUGUCAAAACAAGACUCCUCAUCAUGAUAAGGCUCUUACCCCCUUUUAAUUUGUCCUUGCUUAUGCCUGCCUCUUUCGCUUGGCAGGAUGAUGCUGUCAUUAGUAUUUCACAAGAAGUAGCUUCAGAGGGUAACUUAACAGAGUGUCAGAUCUAUCUUGUCAAUCCCAACGUUUUACAUAAAAUAAGAGAUCCUUUAGUGCACCCAGUGACUGACAUUAGCAGCAUCUUUAACACAGCCGUGUGUUCAAAUGUACAGUGGUCCUUUUCAGAGUUGGACUUCUAGACUCACCUGUUCUCACUCCCUGUUUUAAUUCAACCCAGCCAUGCAAUGCCAAAUAAUAGAAUUGCUCCCUACCAGCUGAACAGGGAGGAGUCUGUGCAGUUUCUGACACUUGUUGUUGAACAUGGCUAAAUACAAUGGGUAUCGCUGAGACUAAGUUGUAGAAAUUAACAAAUGUGCUGCUUGGUUAAAAUGGCUACACUCAUCUGACUCAUUCUUUAUUCUAUUUUAGUUGGUUUGUAUCUUGCCUAAGGUGCGUAGUCCAACUCUUGGUAUUACCCUCCUAAUAGUCAUACUAGUAGUCAUACUCCCUGGUGUAGUGUAUUCUCUAAAAGCUUUAAAUGUCUGCAUGCAGCCAGCCAUCAAAUAGUGAAUGGUCUCUCUUUGGCUGGAAUUACAAAACUCAGAGAAAUGUGUCAUCAGGAGAACAUCAUAACCCAUGAAGGAUAAAAGCCCCAAAUGGUGGUAACUGAUAAUAGCACUAAUGCUUUAAGAUUUGGUCACACUCUCACCUAGGUGAGCGCAUUGAGCCAGUGGUGCUAAAUGCUACAUACUCCAACUGAAAUGUUAAGGAAGAAGAUAGAUCCAAUUAAAAAAAAUUAAAACCAAUUUAAAAAAAAAAAGAACACAGGAGAUUCCAGUCUACUUGAGUUAGCAUAAUACAGAAGUCCCCUCUACUUUAACUUUUACAAAAAAGUAACCUGAACUAAUCUGAUGUUAACCAAUGUAUUUAUUUCUGUGGUUCUGUUUCCUUGUUCCAAUUUGACAAAACCCACUGUUCUUGUAUUGUAUUGCCCAGGGGGAGCUAUCACUGUACUUGUAGAGUGGUGCUGCUUUAAUUCAUAAAUCACAAAUAAAAGCCAAUUAGCUCUAUAACUAAA